AAACAGGCUUACUGUGUUCACUGCUGGACGCCUCUGGGCAAUCUUACCCUCCUGGGAACUGAGAGAGGUAGGUGGAGGUCAGCGUGCUGGGAAACUGGUGGAGGGAGGAAACUGCGGGGAGCUGGUCUUCUCGUGUUACCUCUGUUAAAUCGCUGACAGCAGUUUAAGGUCCAAUAGGCUGGUACUCAAAUGGGCUGCGUGGAUGUUUUAUAUUUCCAGAACCUAGCACAGUGCCGGGCAUAAAACAAUGCUAGGAGCCAGAAACAUGAGGAAUACAUGAGCUCGGCGCCAAUGGAACAUGCUUUCACACCGGGUGCAGCUAACCACCACAUCAUACAAAACUCGUCGCUGACGUUUUAGAUGUAUAAUCUGAUUGGCAUGGACUCACAGAGGAGGGAGUAAGGGAAGAGUAAGAAGAUUUCAAAGGAGAGACACAGGUUGCAGGUUAGCAGGAGAACAGGCAAGCCAAAUGCAAAGGAGCCACUUCAGAAAUGUGUCACAGAAAAGUGAAAAUGCAACCUAGUGGUAAGUGAAGAGGGGAAGAAGAAAGAAAAAGGACCAGAACCGUGAACUGAAGGGACAGGGAACAGCCAGACGAGAGCUUCAGCCAUCACGAGGAUGAUUUCGGAACCUGGAGAAAAUGUAAGUUAAAUAUAUCUACACUCUGAUCCUAUCUCAAGAGAGAGAUAUUUUACUCAUUUCCUGGUUGUGAAUGAUGGGCUCUUGGAAGCACUGUCUUUUUAGCGCGUCUCUUAUCUCUGCCCUGAUUUUUGUAUUUGUUUACAAUACUGAGUUAUGGGAGAAUAAACGUUUUCUGAGGGCAGCUCUGUCCAAUGCUUCACUGUUAGCAGAAGCCUGUCAUCAGAUUUUUGAGGGGAAAGUUUUUUACCCAACAGAAAAUGCAUUGAAAACUACCCUUGAUGAAGCUACCUGCUAUGAGUACAUGGUUCGAAGCCACUAUGUAACAGAAACACUCUCUGAAGAAGAGGCUGGGUUCCCUUUAGCUUACACAGUGACCAUCCACAAAGACUUCGGCACUUUUGAGAGGCUCUUCAGGGCGAUUUAUAUGCCCCAAAAUGUCUACUGUGUGCACCUGGAUCAGAAGGCGACGGAUGCCUUUAAAGGUGCAGUGAAACAGUUACUCAGCUGCUUCCCAAAUGCUUUUCUGGCUUCCAAGAAGGAGUCGGUUGUCUAUGGGGGGAUCUCCAGGCUCCAGGCUGACCUGAACUGCCUGGAAGACCUUGUGGCCUCUGAAGUUCCCUGGAAGUAUGUCAUCAACACCUGCGGGCAAGACUUUCCCCUGAAAACCAACAGGGAAAUAGUUCAGUAUCUGAAGGGAUUUAAAGGGAAAAAUAUCACCCCCGGAGUGCUGCCUCCUGACCACGCUGUUGGACGGACUAAAUACGUCCACCAAGAACUGUUAAACCACAAAAAUUCCUACGUGAUUAAAACAACAAAAUUAAAAACUCCUCCUCCUCAUGACAUGGUGAUUUACUUUGGCACGGCCUACGUGGCUCUCACAAGGGACUUUGCUAACUUCGUCCUCCAAGACCAGCUCGCACUUGACUUACUCUCCUGGUCCAAGGACACCUACAGCCCCGACGAACAUUUCUGGGUGACACUCAACAGGAUUCCCGGUGUUCCUGGCUCUAUGCCAAAUGCAUCCUGGACUGGAAACCUCAGAGCUAUAAAGUGGAGUGACAUGGAAGACAGACACGGAGGCUGCCACGGCCACUAUGUACAUGGUAUUUGUAUCUAUGGAAACGGAGACUUAAAGUGGCUGGUUAAUUCACCAAGCCUGUUUGCUAACAAGUUUGAGCUUAAUACCUACCCCCUUACUGUGGAAUGCCUAGAACUGAGGCAUCGCGAAAGAACCCUCAAUCAGAGUGAAACUGCGAUACAACCCAGCUGGUAUUUUUGAGCUAUUCAUGAGCUACUCAUGACUGAAGGGAAACUGCAGCUGGGAAGAGGAGCCUGUUUUUGUGAGAGACUUUUGCCUUCGUAAUGUUAACCGUUUCAGGACCACGUUUAUAGCUUCAGGACCUGGCUACGUAAUUAUACUUAAAAUAUCCACUGGACACUGUGAAAUACACUAACAGGAUGGCUGGGUAGAGCAAUCUGGGCACUUUGGCCAAUUUUAGUCUUGCUGUUUCUUGAUGCUCACCUCUAUAUUAGUUUAUUGUUAGGAUCAAUGAUAAAUUUAAAUGACCUCAGAUCUUUGCACCAGAUACUCAUCAUAUACAAAUGUUUUAGUAAAAAAGAGAAUUGUAGAUAAUACUGUCUAGGAAAAUAAGAAUUAGGUUUCUUUGAAGAAGGAAUCUUUUAUAACACCUUAACAGUCACCACUGUGCUCAACCAGACAGAUAGUGAAACAGCUUUCUGGGUAAUUCACCAAUUUCCUUUAAAACAUAAGCUACCUGAAUGGAGAAUACAUCUUGUUUCUGAGUUUCAACACUAGCAUUUUUGGCUUACUCAUGGACAAAGUUCUGUAUAUAGUAUAAAGUCAUUAACAAGAAACAGGAUAUGCUUUAAGACAGAAUUCACUGUCUGUUGCUUCAGUAAAAGGACCUCGGGGAAUAAAACAUUUCUCUCUUAUAUGCCAGAAUGUAGGCUGGUCCCUAUGUCAUGUCUUCCAUUAAGAACACUAAAAAGUCCUUGCAAGAAUGGAGAUAUGCAUUCAAGAGAGGUGCUAUCACAUAGAUCUAGUCUGAAGUCUGGAACACUUUCCUCUUCUAUGACCCCUCUCUCCCCAGUAUUAUCUUACUUGCAAAAUGGAGACCAAAUUCUAUCCUGUGAGGCUUUUAAUUGCACCAUAGUAUGCUCUGAGUAGCUUUACACUGCCUGGUACUGAUAGUAGUGGCUCGAUUUUUAAGAGCCUUCAAUUGUAGAUGAACAUCUCUGUUAUUUAUCCCUCAUUCAUCCAUCCGUUCAUUCAUUCAGCCUUCAAUCAACAUCUCUUGAGUGUCUAUUAUGUACAGGACAUGUACUGAGACAAAAAGGAAACAUAAGAGCUUUUUCACUCUAAAAAUCUUGGCAAUAAUGUCAACACCAGAAAGCCUCCUCUGGAGAAUCUUACAGAGUGAUUGUAGUUUAAUACAGGAACACACAGGGCUGUGUAGCAUGAUACCAGGCCCAGGAGAUCAGUAAUUACAAAUUAAGGGUUAAAUCAGAGAUUAUUCAACAGAGAGGGAGAAAGGAGGAGACAGAGGGAGGACCUGUUGUGUUCCAGCCAUUCUGGUAUUCCUUUAUGUAUCUAAUUUCAUUCAAACCUCACAACAGUCUUGUGAGGCCCUUAUAUAAUUACUCCCAUUUUGCAGAUGAAGUAACUGAGGCUUAGAAAGGUUAAUAGCACCGGGGAACAAUUUCUCUGGGUGAGAAUUGGGACUCUGUUGCUGGUCUUCUCAGUUCAUUUCCUGAGGUGGAUUUACUGAGAGAAGGUGAAAUAAAGCCAUAUUUAGUAUACCAGAGAAGGUAGAUUUUAAGAAUGGUCUCAGUGUUAAUACUGAGAAAAAGUCCUGUCAGUUCAGAAAAAAUGUGAAGUCUACUUUAGUAUUCCUGUAAUACUAAACCGUUGAGUUUCUAAAUAUUUAUUUAUUCUAACAAAAAGCAAUUACUACAAAUGGAUGACACAUUUAAUGAACACAAUUUUAUUUUUUUUCUGUAACUGUGCUUGUUGAAUGUCAAUCAUAUUUAAAGGGAAUGACUUUGAAGUAAAACCUUUUUUCUUGCUACUGAAAAAAAUGGAGUUGUUUUGGGUGGUAAAGUGUUAAGGAAUAGGGACAGCUGGUCACACAAGGAACUCUUGAAGGCCACAUGUGAAAACCUGUCACUUGCACAGAGGCCAGUCCCACUAAGGUGACCAGAGUGGGCUCCAAGCACAAACUGCCAUUGGCUAUAGAUGGGACUGUGUCCCCCCAAAAUUCAUGUGUUGGAGCCUUAACCCUCAAUGUGAUGGUAUUUGAGAUGGGGCCUUUGGUAAGGGAAGUUUAGAUGAGGUCACGAGGGUAGGACCCUCAUGAUGGGAUGAGUCCCCUUACAAGACCUCUGGCUUGGGCCGGGCGUGGUGGCUCACACCUGUAAUCCCAACACUUUGGGAGGCCAAGGCAGGUAGAUCACUUGAUGCCAGGAGUUCCAGACCAGGCUGGCCGACAUGGUGAAACCCCAUCUCUACUAAAAAAUAUAAAAAUUAGCCGGGCUUUGUGGCAUGUGCCUGUAAUCCCAGCUAUUUGGCAGGCUGAGGCAUGAGAAUCGCUUGAACCCAGGAGGUGGAGGUUACAGUGAGCUGAGAGUGCCCCACUGCACUCCAGCCUGGGUGACAGAGCGAGACUUUGUCCCAAAACAAAAUAGGUGAGGGGAUAGCGAAUGCACUCAGGGUCAGCAGUGGAGUUUAAAAAUUGUCUCUUUUCAACUUAUUUAAAUGACAGCACCUGAGAAGAGGAACCGUUUUACACUGGAUGUUUCUCAUGUAGAACAAGAAAUCUUUCUGGAAUUGAUGUUUACAUGUCUGUUGUUGGUCAUCUCUCCUGUGUCUUAAAUACUUUAAUGUUGGAAGAGCAUAGUGUUUGGGCUAGUGGGUUUCUGACAGCCCAUGGGAAUGCCCUGAAACUACUGUAUCUGAUGUUUGUUUUCGAUGAGGUUCCAUGUUUUGUUUUCUUGGGAAUAAAUUAAUAUAUUGUUUUCCA